AUGCGAGGUUUCAACAAAACCACUGUGGUUACACAGUUCAUCCUGGUGGGUUUCUCCAGCCUGGGGGAGCUCCAGCUGCUGCUUUUUGUCAUCUUUCUUCUCCUAUACUUGACAAUCCUGGUGGCCAAUGUGACCAUCAUGGCCGUUAUUCGCUUCAGCUGGACUCUCCACACUCCCAUGUAUGGCUUUCUAUUCAUCCUUUCAUUUUCUGAGUCCUGCUACACUUUUGUCAUCAUCCCUCAGCUGCUGGUCCACCUGCUCUCAGACACCAAGACCAUCUCCUUCAUGGCCUGUGCCACCCAGCUGUUCUUUUUCCUUGGCUUUGCUUGCACCAACUGCCUCCUCAUUGCUGUGAUGGGAUAUGAUCGCUAUGUAGCAAUUUGUCACCCUCUGAGGUACACACUCAUCAUAAACAAAAGGCUGGGGUUGGAGUUGAUUUCUCUCUCAGGAGCCACAGGUUUCUUUAUUGCUUUGGUGGCCACCAACCUCAUUUGUGACAUGCGUUUUUGUGGCCCCAACAGGGUUAACCACUAUUUCUGUGACAUGGCACCUGUUAUCAAGUUAGCCUGCACUGACACCCAUGUGAAAGAGCUGGCUUUAUUUAGCCUCAGCAUCCUGGUAAUUAUGGUGCCUUUUCUGUUAAUUCUCAUAUCCUAUGGCUUCAUAGUUAACACCAUCCUGAAGAUCCCCUCAGCUGAGGGCAAGAAGGCCUUUGUCACCUGUGCCUCACAUCUCACUGUGGUCUUUGUCCACUAUGGCUGUGCCUCUAUCAUCUAUCUGCGGCCCAAGUCCAAGUCUGCCUCAGACAAGGAUCAGUUGGUGGCAGUGACCUACACAGUGGUUACUCCCUUACUUAAUCCUCUUGUCUACAGUCUGAGGAACAAAGAGGUAAAAACUGCAUUGAAAAGAGUUCUUGGAAUGCCUGUGGCAACCAAGAUGAGCUAA